ACUCUUUCCUGCUGCCUAGUCUGCUGAGCAGAGCUUCAGUCUCCACCAUCAAUCAUCCAGUGAGGAAUUUGCACUUACACAAGGAACUCUUCCUCGGAGAGAUCCCCUCCUGAACCCACCUGCAGUUCACCAGCCCCAGACCAAGAGCACCUUCUCUAUGCCUCUCUGAAAUGUCCAUCCACUCCAGAGAACCAGCCCCUGACACCCACCCCCUUGCCCUGCCUGCACCGAUUGUGCAAGGAGGGAAGGUCAACAGAGCCAAGUCCAUUGAGGGAUAUCAAGAGAAGCCAGAGUAAACCCUUGAUCUGCGCCAUCUUGUCUGCUCGUGGCUGACAAAGAGAAGGGAAGAUGGAGCCACCAUCUUGAAAACUUCUAGUCCUUAGUUCCUGCCGGCAUUCACCCGUGCAAGCUCCCAGCUUGUUUGUGUCUGCAGCUCGCCUUUACAGGAUGCUCUUUGUUAGAAAAUGAUUUGGGGCUGCUUUUCAUUAAAAAGAAAAGCCUCACUGAGGACUCCCAUAACCUUACUAUCUGCGUCUGACCAGGGAUUCUGCAUUUAAAGAAACUCUUGUUGAUCUUGUUGGUUCAUGGACAACACUUUGAGAAGCCAGGCUAUAGAGGGUACAAGUAUUAUGGAACUAACACUACAUUUCCAGAUCCCGAUGGUAGCAAAGAAAAGGAUGGAAGAAUUUCAGAUGCCCCAGAAAAAGACAGCAAGAAAAAGUUAUUUUAUCCCCAUGGAAACAGGAAAUCAAACACAUGCCCAAGAAUUUCUCCUCCUGGGAUUUUCAGCAACGUCAGAGAUUCAGUUCAUUCUCUUUGGGCUGUUCCUCUCCAUGUACCUAGUCACUUUCACCGGGAACCUGCUCAUCAUCCUGGCCAUAUGCUCAGACUCCCACCUCCACACCCCCAUGUACUUCUUCCUCUCCAACCUGUCUUUUGCUGACCUCUGUUUUACCUCCACGACUGUCCCAAAGAUGUUACUGAAUAUACUGACACAGAACAAAUUCAUAACAUAUGCAGGCUGUCUCAGUCAGAUUUUUUUUUUCACUUCAUUUGGAUGCCUGGACAAUUUACUCUUGACCGUGAUGGCCUAUGACCGCUUCGUGGCCGUCUGUCACCCCCUGCACUAUACGGUCAUCAUGAACCCCCAGCUCUGUGGACUGCUGGUUCUGGGGUCCUGGUGCAUCAGUGUCAUGGGUUCCCUGCUCGAGACCUUGACUGUUUUGAGGCUGUCCUUCUGCACCGAAAUGGAAAUUCCACACUUUUUUUGUGAUCUACUUGAAGUCCUGAAGCUCGCCUGUUCUGACACCUUCAUUAAUAACGUGGUGAUAUACUUUGCAACUGGCGUCCUGGGUGUGAUUUCCUUCACUGGAAUAUUUUUCUCUUACUAUAAAAUUGUUUUCUCUAUACUGAGGAUUUCCUCAGCUGGGAGAAAGCACAAAGCGUUUUCCACCUGUGGUUCCCACCUCUCAGUGGUCACCUUGUUCUAUGGCACGGGCUUUGGGGUCUAUCUCAGUUCUGCAGCCACACCAUCUUCUAGGACAAGUCUGGUGGCCUCAGUGAUGUACACCAUGGUCACCCCCAUGCUGAACCCCUUCAUCUACAGCCUGAGGAACACGGACAUGAAGAGGGCCCUGGGGAGACUCCUCAGUAGGGCAACAUUUUUUAAUGGUGACAUCACUGCAGGACUUUCAUAAGUAGCAAGGCUUGGACCAUUGGGAGGCACUUUUGGUGGUUCUUGAAUGUAUCCAAACAUCAAUGUAUUCUCUUUUAGUUCUGGAAUUACCAUAUCUUAUCGUGUCUUUGAUACAGGAGCUAGAAAGAAAUUAUUUAGGUAGAUAGGGAGGGCCACAGAGUCCUUGGCAAGGUUUCCCCGUUAACAAAAAGCAGCCCUCAAAAUCAUUUCUUUUCUAACAAAGAACAGCCUGAAAAAUCGAGCUGCAGACAUAGAUAAGCAAGCUGGAAGCUUGCAUGAGUGAAUGCCGGCUGCUGCGCCAAUAGAAAAGGGCUAGCUGGGGACCAGUCAUGUUCAACAUGGAGGCUCCCUCUUCCUUUUCUUUGUCAACCAUGUGUACAGCAAAGGAACAGGCAACAUGGGGCUGCCCAGGUAAAGAACCCAUCUGUAUAAUAAAAGAUUAGGGUGGGGCAGCCAGCUUCUCCACAUGCUAUGCAAAUGGCACACCUGAUCCAACCAAUCUUUUAUGGCCUAUGUAAAUCAGACAACACCUCCUCAAGCUAGUUUAUAAAACCCUGUGCAUUUCACCAUGGAACUGGCAACCCAUUUUCUCUGGGACCCCUCUCUGCACAUAGAGCUCUUCUCUUUCUCUCACCUAUUAAACUUCUGCUCUUAACCUCA